GGACCCGGAGGUCGCGGAGAGCUGGGCAGUGUUGGCCGCUGGCGGAGCGCUGGGGCAGCAUGAAGUGCCUGGUCACGGGCGGCAACGUGAAGGCUCUCCCUCCGGACGGUGAACUCCUCCCGCUCUGCCUAUGCCUGCUUUCUCUUUGCCCCGCUCUUCUUCCAGCAAUACCAGGCAGCCACCCCUGGUCAGGACCUGCUGCGCUGUAAGAUCCUGAUGAAGGUGAGGCCCUUCCCUCAGCAGUGGCACUACUCCACCCCAGGAAUCUCCACCAGCUGUGCCUCUGCCCUGGGGUACUCAGUAGAUGCUAAGUGGGGAGAGAGACACGUGCAAGCCCAAUCCAUGCAAAACACAGGGAGGGCCAUGGUAAAAGCAUCACAGCGGGGACCUGAGAGGGUGGUGACGCUCAAGUUCGUCAAGAAAGGUAAGCACGUCUUUUGGCCGGGCGCGGUGGCUCACGCCUGUAAUCCCAGCACUUUGGGAGGCCGAGGCAGGCGGAUCACGAGGUCAGGAGUUCGAGACCAGCCUGGCCAACAUGGCGAAACCCCGUCUCUACUAAAAAUACAAAAAUUAGCUGGGCGUGGUGGCACGCGCCUGUAAUCCCAGCUACUCGGGAGGCUGAGGCAGGAGAAUUGCUUGAAUCCGGGAGGUGGAGGUUGCAGUGAGCUGAGAUCGCACCACUGCACUCCAGCCUGGGUGACAGAGCGAGACUCCAUCUCAAAAAAAAAAAAAAAAAAGGUAAGCAGGUCUUUCAAGGCAUUCCAAGCAUAAGGAAGAGCAUGAAUGAGGCCUAGAAGGAUGCCAGUGCCCGAGGUGACGUGGGAGCCCUUUUCCCAGAGUUACAUGCUGGGCCCAUGAUGGGUGUGGGCCUGCAUGGGACAGGAGAGCUUGUUGCAGAGAUGUGAUGCUAGGCUGAGGUGUCUUAUCCCAUGCAGUCUUUCCUGUCUGUCUUCCGCUCACUGGCGAUGCUGGAGAAGACGGUGGAAAAAUGCUGCAUCUCCCUGAAUGGCCGGAGCAGCCGCCUGGUGGUCCAGCUGCAUUGCAAGUUCGGGGUGCGGAAGACUCACAACCUGUCCUUCCAGGACUGUGAGUCCCUGCAGGCCGUCUUCGACCCAGCCUCGUGCCCCCACAUGCUCCGCGCCCCAGCACGGGUUCUGGGGGAGGCUGUUCUGCCCUUCUCUCCUGCACUGGCUGAAGUGACGCUGGGCAUUGGCCGUGGCCGCAGGGUCAUCCUGCGCAGCUACCACGAGGAGGAGGCAGACAGCACUGCCAAAGCCAUGGUGACUGAGAUGUGCCUUGGAGAGGAGGAUUUCCAGCAGCUGCAGGCCCAGGAAGGGGUGGCCAUCACUUUCUGCCUCAAGGAAUUCCGGGGGCUCCUGAGCUUUGCAGAGUCAGCAAACUUGAAUCUUAGCAUUCAUUUUGAUGCUCCAGGCAGGCCCGCCAUCUUCACCAUCAAGGACUCUUUGCUGGACGGCCACUUUGUCUUGGCCACACUCUCAGACACCGACUCGCACUCCCAGGACCUGGGCUCCCCAGAGCGUCACCAGCCAGUGCCUCAGCUCCAGGCUCACAGCACACCCCACCCGGACGACUUUGCCAAUGACGACAUUGACUCUUACAUGAUCGCCAUGGAAACCACUAUAGGCAAUGAGGGCUCGCGGGUGCUGCCCUCCAUUUCCCUUUCACCUGGCCCCCAGCCCCCCAAGAGCCCCGGUCCCCACUCCGAGGAGGAAGAUGAGGCUGAGCCCAGUACAGUGCCUGGGACUCCCCCACCCAAGAAGUUCCGCUCACUGUUCUUCGGCUCCAUCCUGGCCCCUGUACGCUCCCCCCAGGGCCCCAGCCCUGUGCUGGCGGAAGACAGUGAGGGUGAAGGCUGAACCAAGAACCUGAAGCCUGUACCCAGAGGCCUUGGACUAGACGAAGCCCCAGCCAGUGGCAGAACUGGGUCUCUCAGCCCUGGGGAUCAGAAAGGUGGGCUUGCUGGAGCUGAGCUGUUUCACUGCCUCUCGCAGGCCCCAGCUGGCUGUCACUGUAAAGCUGUCCCACAGCGGUCGGGCCUGGGCCGUUAUCUCCCCACAACCCCCAGCCAAUCAGGACUUUCCAGACUUGGCCCUGAACUACUGACGUUCCUACCUCUUAUUUCUCAUUGAGCCUCAGGCUAUACUCCAGCUGGCCAAGGCUGGAAACCUGUCUCCCUCAGGCUCACCUUCCUAAGGAAAAUGUCAUAGUAGGUGCUGCUGGCCCCUGGUGAUCCAGCUUCUCUGCCAAUCAUGACCUGUUCCUUCCUGAAGUCCUGGGCAUGCAUCUGGGACCCCCGUGGAGCUGACAAGUUUUCCUUGCUUUCCUGAUACUCUUUGGCGCUGACUUGGAAUUCUAAGAGCCUUGGACCCGAGUGUGUGGCUAGGGUUGCCCUGGCUGGGGCCCGGUGCCGAGACUCCCAAGCGGCUCUGUGCAGAAGAGCUGCCAGGCAGUGUCUUAGAUGUGAGACGGAGGCCAUGGCGAGAAUCCAGCUUUGACCUUUAUUCAAGAGACCAGAUGGGUUGCCCCAGGAUCCGGCUGCCAGCCCUGAGGCCAAGCACGGCUGGAGACCCACGACCUGGCCUGCCGUUGCCCUGAGCUGCAGCCUCGGCCCCAGGAUCCUGCUCACAGUCACCGCAGGUGCAGGCAGGAAGCAGCCCUGGGGGACUGGACGCUGCUAUUGAUUCAUUAAAAAAAGAAAAGAAAAAUACA